UGAGCAAGAACAGCCAUGAGUGCCCCAGAAGCUUACAGCCCAGCGGGGCGCAGAGAGGACACAACGCUAUCAUCAAAGAAUUACUUCAUUGCAGUGGCACCAAGUGCUGCAGAGAAAAACAACAAGAGCGUCUAGCCAGGGACCGUCCUGGUUAGAGGGGCAGCAAAGGCCCCUAUAAGUCUCAUUGAACCUGUGACUUGACAGAGUAGGAGAAGUCAGGCGAAGGCAGGAGAGGAAUGUUCUAGGCUGUGCAGACGAGAGCUGGAGUGUGGAGAGACACAUGACUUGGUCAGACAAACCUGGGUUCAAAUCCUGGCUCCUCCCCUGCUUCCUAGCUGUGUGACGCAGGGCACACAGUCAACCUCUCUGUGCUGCCGUGUCUUCACCUCAGUUAACAGCCACUGUCUCGUCAGGAUGUUGUGUAAGAUGAGGUAUCUGGAAACACUCCCCACAGGACCCCGUUUUCAGUGAGGGCUCAGAAAGUGUUUGCUGAAUGGCUGUAAAGAGCGUUACCUGGGUCUCAUUUCGGAGCAAGUAAACAUGGCCUUUGUUUUAAUAUUUGUUAAGUCCCUGCCGGGCGCAGGGAGGGGUGAAAGUUUAGGCUCUUGUGCCCCAAAACGGCCCAGCCACCUGGAAGCCUCCAGGACGCCACAGCUGAGAGCAAGCGAAGAUCCUGGGCCAGGGUCAAGGGAGGCUGCCCACGGGAAGGAGAAGUCAGUGCUAGGCUUGGAGACAGAUGGAGCUUGGCUAGGGCUUGAGGAGCCGGGCAGAAGUUCUGAGUGGAGGGCACAGCUAAGGUAGCGGCUGGGAGGUUAUGGCUGGCCCUUCCCACCUGCAGCGUGGGGGUGGGAGGGAGGGGAGAGGGAGGCAGCUCCCAGGAGUCGAAGGCCCCCAGGGGCAGGUCCAACCCAGUCUCUGCUCAGCUUGGCCUUAACGGCGGCACCCCCAGAUCUCCAUCCAGUUCCUGGUGUACAGGCGCAGCACCGCCGCCUCGGAGCUUGAGCCCCUCCUCCCCAGCUGACCAGAACCAGGCUGAGCGCAGGAGGACAGGCACCACCGGAUGCCACACCAGGCAGGAGGAGGUGUGGACAGUGAUGGUACGGCGGCCCUGCAUCAGCCUGCGGGUGGCCUCUGGAUCCUCCGUGGACCGAACCGUCCCCCCAGGAACACACCUUCAGGGGCCACAGCCACAGCCUGCUGGACUCAGGACUGUCCUGUCAACUCCAGACAACUGAAUAAACAGGCCGGGUACAGUGGCUCGCACCUGUAAUCCUAGCACUUUGGGAGGCCGAAGCGGGUGGACCACUUGACGUCCGUAGUUCGAGACCAGCCUGGCCAACAUGGUGAAACCCCAUCUCUACUAAAAAUACAAAAAUUAGCCAGGUGUGGUGGCACACAUCUGUAGUCCCAGCUACUUGGGAGGCUGAGGCAGGAGAACUGUUUGAACCUGGGAGACAGAGGUUGCGGUGAACCGAGAUCGUGCCACUGUACUCCAGCCUGGGUGACAGAGUGAGACUCCGUCUCAAAAAAAUAAAAAAGAUAACCGAGGAAACGGUACCUCCCCAUGAGACCUGCUUCUGUUGCUCCUUCCCCAAGGUGCUGAGGGAUCGGGGCUGCUUUGGGGACCAGCGGUGGAUGUGGAUGGGGAUUCAGGACGAGCUGAGCAGAGGGGACCGCAUCUGCCUGCAGCCCUGGCCCAGCCUCCUGGGGCCUCUGGUUUCUUUAGCCUGCUUCUCCGGGCCCUUUCCUGACAGGCCCCACACCUUACUGUGGGGACAUAGCAGGGAGAGUGACUCCCCACGGGGAGCCUGCCCCUCGGUGUUCAGGAAGAAGCAGAAUGGUUAAGGUUCUGUUGGAUCUGGGUUCUCCAUCGCAGUUCCUCAGUGCCUAGCUUAUCUCAUCUGUGAAAUGGACAGUACUGUCAUUUCCUGUGUCCUUUCAAGGAUUACAUAAGAUGCUGACAUUAUGGAGUUUAGCCCCAGAUCUGGCGCAUAGUAAGGGCUCAAUAAAGGUUAGUUUUGAGGACUUUUAGUUGGAGAAGAGGAGCAACCAGAUCUUGGAGAUCAGGGAGAGCCUCCUGGAGGAGGUGAUAGGUCAGAAGGAUGAGCGGGAGAUAUCACAGGGAAAGAGGGAGGAUUGAAGGCAGGAGGAAGAAGUGGCGGGUACAGGAGCAAGGUGGGAGAGUGGAGAGGAGGGCAGAGCUGAGCUCCGAGUGCUUCCUGGACCCGCAAACUCAGUGUUGUCCAGACCCUGUUUUAUUUUUAAAAUUUUUUAGCCCAGGCCGGAGUACAGUGGUGCGAUCAUAGCUCACUGCAGCCUCGAACUCCUAGCUUCCAGGGAUCCUCCCACUCAGCCUCCCGAGGAGCUGGGACUACAGAUGAGCACCACCAUGCCUGGCUCCAGACCCUGUUCUGAUUCCACUUUCCUGGGGGUCAUGACCCUCAGGUGCCUGGAGCACAGAGACGCCAGCUCCCCACCUUGUUGGCCUGAUCUCACCCCACACACCCAACCCUAGCUGUGGAAAACCAGAACCAGGGACUUGGGGUAUCUGGUGGGGUAGUCUUGGGGAGAGACGCUGCGUCCCAGAGUGGGCCUUGCCUUUAGGAUCUCCCUUCCCAGCCCCGGAGAAGGGAAACGGUGCCAUGGCCAUUCUGGUGCCGCAGAUCCUUUGUGAGCACAGCCCUCCACUCAGCCUUUGCUGUGUCAGACACCGGGGCUGUGGUGAACCAGCUCCAAGGCCCUGCCUUCCAGGAGAGGAGAUGGUUACCAUGACCAGAAGGUAGAAAUGUCAGGAAAUGAGCAGAUGAGACCAGCCCCAGGAGGGUCAAUCAGGGAGGACUUCUCAGAGGAGUGGCCUUUGAGCUGGAUCUUGAAGGCAGAGGGGAGGGCAGUUCAGGAAAAGGGAGGGGCAGGUACAGAGGCCUGGAGGUGGGUGUCUCGGGUGCUUCCAAGGUGGGGCUGCUUACAAGGAGCCUUGAAAGCCACACCAAUGCCAAGGACAAGGUCCUGGGGCACACCCAGCAGCAGCCCAGCAGCAGGUGAUGGGGUUUGGUCGGGUGAAGAGCCUUUUGCUAGAGAGAGGAGGCAAGGCACACCUCUGAGACCCAGGUGGGCAGAGAGGGCCAGUCUCCCCUGCCCUGUCCCCCUAGGGGACACCCACGGAGCCCAGGAUGCCAUCUGGCAUGCAGCUGUUAGUUGCACACUUGCCAUGUGCGGGCUGCGCCGCCUGCCAUCAGUGCACGAGAUCUCCCCGUCUUCACAGCCAGCUCUGAGAUGGGGGAGUUUUUAUUUUUUUUUGACACAGAGUCUUGCUCUGCCGCCCAAGCUGGAGUGCAAUGGUGCGAUCUCAGCUCACUGCAACCUCCGCCUCCCGGGUUCGAGCGAUUCUCCUGCCUCAACCUCCCAAGUAGCUGGGAUUACAGGCGCCUGCCGCCACGCUCAGCUAAUUUUUGUAUUUUUAGUAGAGACGGGGUUUCACCAUGUUGGCCAGGCUGGUCUCGAACUCCUUACCUCAGGUGAUCUGCUUGCCUCAGCCUCUCAAAGUGCUGGGAUUACAGGUGUGCCACCGCGCCCGGCCAAGAUGGGAGUAUUUUUAUGGCCAUUUUACAGAUGGGAGAACAGUCUCAGCACAAUUGAGCAGCUUGCCCAGCUAGGAGCAGCAGCAACACGAGACCCUCCAGCUUUGGGAGCCACCCCACACCUGGCCAACGCUGGCGGCCCGUGUCCCCUUCCUCCAUCCUUGCUGGGGGCCCAUGGCUUGUGGCAGUUCAGCUUCACCCUCAGGAGUGGCCCGAACCCUGCUGGACCCAGGCUCCCUUCUCACCAUCCUGAAUAGCGACUUUGCUGAGCCUCUGGCCCUGCCGAGAUUUCAGGAUAAGUUACCCCCAGGCCCGAAGCCCCAGCUUGCCCUGGCCUGUGCCUGCCUCAGGUGCCAGCUAGAUGUCUCGCUCCACCUGGGUCUGGGACCUGGCUCCACACCAGUUACCUGGGACCAGUAGGUGCCCUUCCAGCCUGAAGAUCUGGGGGCACAGUAUAGCCACAUGAGCCCCAAGUGUGGUCCUGAACUGGGGCCGGGUGGGGAAGAGUGAGAUGGGAUAACAUAGCCCCUGCUUGGAGGCCCUUCUCUGAUGGGGUGACAUAAUCCCUUCCUCCUGGGAAACACCAGCUUUUGGGGUGAUAGCACUUUCAGGCAGGAGCUAUGGUUCCUUCCUCAGGAGGCCUCCAAUCUGAUGGGGAAGACAUGGCCCCUCCCCCUGGGGAGUGCCCUGUGUGAUGGAGGCGAUACAGCCCCUACCUUCAGAGAGCACCUGGCCUGCAGCUCAUCCAAACCUGAGUCUCCUCUCCCUUGGAGGCCUCAUUCCAGCGCCCCAAGGAGGAUUCAAACUGUUGGGGCUGGAAGAACUUGGUGGCCUGGGUCCCUGGAGCCCUGUUGAAGGAGCUGGUGACAUUCUGAUGCUGGAGGCAGGUGACGGGGAGCACAGACUUUGUGUCCUGCACACUGAGCUCCAAGUGUGCCCCAGCCACUGAGCCUUGUGACUUGAGCAGAUGUCCGAAGCCGUUUCUUCAUCCCAUGAGACCAACAACACUGUCUGCCUCAGAACAUAGCCGUGAUCAAGAUGAGCACGGAGGCUCGUGUCCCAGCACCUGGCACACAGUAAGUGCCUGGUAAAUAAACAAUGGCUAUAUUUGCUUGUCAUCAGGGGGCUUACCAAUGCCUGGAACCUCCCCCAGGUUCCUCACAAAGAGAAGGGCCAAGGCCGGGUGCAGUGGUUCACGCCUGUAUUCCCAGCAUUUUGGGAGGCUGAGGCAGGAGGAUCACUUGAGCCAAGGAGUUCAAGACCAACUUGGGCAACAUAGCAAGACCCCAUCUCUACAAAAAUUUAAAAAAUUACAAUAAAGGCGAAUCUCAUCGAUGGGAUUCUGCCAUACUGAUGGGGCCGUGUUUGCUGAUGGUGGGCAAACAUGUUACCAAGUUAAACGCCUCCACAGGUGGCUUCCCUUUCUCCCUGGCUUACACCUCCUGCUCCUUCCUGCAGGUCAUGGGAUGGCAGGAUGCUUGUCUCCAGGUGUGGCCUGAAGGGAAAAGUGUGGACAGUUUGGUGUGAUCAAGGAAAUGGAACCACGCUUACCAGUUGCCCUUGUCCAGGAAGGGCUGGCUCCCUUAGGACGCCCACAUGGAGCAUGAGGUUGGGCCAGGCACCCCCAGAGGUCCCCGCCUUGGCAGGUUCUGUUUUACCUGUUGAACGAGACACUGUAUGGGGAAGUGACAUGCGCAGUGCCUGGCCCAGUGCUGUGCACACACGCUGCUUCGCUUCCUCAGGUUCCGGGGAUGGGAUGGGACAGAAAAGCUGGUUGCUUAGCUGGUGGCGUUCUCCAGCAAAGCAGAAGGGAUGGUCCUGGCAGCCCUGUGCCGAGCACUGGACCCCGCGCCCUCCCUGGCUCUCUCAGCCCCAAGGUCCCAUUAGUUAUCAAACCUGGUUUUUUGUUUUUGUUUUGAGACAGAGUCACUCCGUCACCCAGGCUGGAGUGCAGUGGUACGAUCUUGGCUUACUGCAGCCUCCACCUCCUGGGCUCAAGUGAUCCUCCCACUUGAGUGCCACCACGCCCAGCUAGUUUUUGUAUUUUUGGUAGAGAUGGGGUUUCGCCAUGUUGCCCAGCAGGCUGUUCUCAAACUCCUAAGCUCAAGUGAUCCUCCCACCUCAGCCUCCCAAAUUUGCUGGGAUUCCAGGGUUUUGAAGCCACAGCCAAGACGACAUGGCCUUCCAUUCCUGAAGCCGAGGAAGGGGAGAAAGCCACAACCUUCACCACUCUCCACCCUUUCUGUCUGUGUGACUUGGCUUUCAUCGGAGCUGAAUGACGGGACCCCAGAGGUGCCGGGUGACAGCCAGGUGCAGAGCCUCAACUACCCCAGAUGGUAAAGCUUUAAACUGAUCCACUGGCCAGGUGAGGCGACUCAUGCCUGGAAUCCCAACACUUUGGGAGGCUGAGGCAGGUGGAUUGCGUAAGCUGAGUUCAAGACCAGCCUGGGCAACGUGGUGGUGUGCACCUGUAGACCUAGCUACCUGGGAGGUUAAGGUGGGAGGAUUGCUUGGGCCCUGGAGGUCAAGGCUGCAGUGAGUCAAGACAGCACCACUGCACUCCAGCCUGGGUGACAGAGACCUUGUCUCAAACAAAACAAAACAAAACAAAACAAAACAAAACAAAACACAGGAAAACCUGGAUCUGCUUAGCAUUGGCCCUAGGGCAGGGAGUGGGUUACCUUCCACCGUGGAUUAACUCAGUUCAACUGAUAACUACUCCUCCAGGCCCCCAGCCUGGGACAGCCCUGGGGACACAGUCACCCAGUAGCAGCACUGUGCCCAGCACAGGUAAGCACUCAAUAAUGACGACGGUUACUAAGUACUCCACCCCCACCAAACAGUAGGCAGAGACUGUCUCUCCUGUUGGCCAUCAUAACCCCAGUACUCAGUAGGCGCUGAAUGUUUGGUGAAUGAGUAAGUGAAGGGAAAGCUGAGGCACCAACCCUCAGGGAGCCCUCAGUCUGGUGGAUGUAACCAACAACCACAGAACUACAGAACUGUAUACUUUAGAUACAUGAAUUGUGUGGUAUGUGAAUUAUAUCUCAAAGCCAUUUGAAAAAAUACCAAAUGUGCCAUUAAGAUUUGGAUGGGAAGUUAUGGGUAAUGAGAAUAUAAUGACAUCUUGCAACAUUAUAUUGAGAAAAAUACAAA